ACCCCUGACACCAUGACCCACUGUUGCUCCCCUUGCUGUCAGCCUACCUGCUGCAGGACCACCUGCUGCAGGACCACCUGCUGGAAGCCCACCACUGUGACCACCUGCAGCAGCACACCCUGCUGCCAGCCCGCCUGCUGUGUGUCCAGCUGCUGCCAGCCUUGCUGCCGCCCAACUUGCUGUCAAAACACCUGCUGUAGGACCACCUGCUGCCAGCCCACCUGUGUGACCAGCUGCUGCCAGCCUUCCUGCUGCAGCACAACCUGCUGCCAGCCCACCUGCUGUGGGUCCAGCUGCUGUGGCCAAACCAGCUGUGGGUCCAGCUGUGGCCAGAGCAGCUCCUGUGCACCUGUGUACUGCAGAAGAACCUGCUACUACCCCACGACUGUCUGCCUGCCUGGUUGCCUAAACCAGAGCUGUGGCUCCAACUGCUGCCAGCCGUGCUGCCGCCCAGCCUGCUGUGAGACCACCUGCUGCAGGACCACUUGCUUCCAGCCCACCUGUGUGUCCAGCUGCUGCCAGCCUUCUUGCUGCUGA